GAGAGCCAUUUCAACGUGAGCCCCCAGUCUGAGAACAAGAAAGAAGAACUUCUGUCUCGAGGGUCUCACUGUCAACCAGGCCAGAGUGCAGUGAAGAUCAUACCUCACUACAUCCGUGAACUCCCGGGCUCCUCCCACCUAAGUCUCUUGAGUAGCUGGGACUUCAGGAGACUGAAGCCAAGGAUACCAGCAGAGCCAACAUUUGCUUCAAGUUCCUGGGCCUGCUGACAGCGUGCAGGAUGCUGUUGGAACCCGGCAGAGGCUGCUGUGCCCUGGCCAUCCUGCUGGCAAUUGUGGACAUCCAGUCUGGUGGAUGCAUUAACAUCACCAGCUCAGCUUCCCAGGAAGGAACGCGACUAAACUUAAUCUGUACUGUAUGGCAUAAGAAAGAAGAGGCUGAGGGGUUUGUAGUGUUUUUGUGCAAGGACAGGUCUGGAGACUGUUCUCCUGAGACCAGUUUAAAACAGCUGAGACUUAAAAGGGAUCCUGGGAUAGAUGGUGUUGGUGAAAUAUCAUCUCAGUUGAUGUUCACCAUAAGCCAAGUCACACCGUUGCACAGUGGGACCUACCAGUGUUGUGCCAGAAGCCAGAAGUCAGGUAUCCGCCUUCAGGGCCAUUUUUUCUCCAUUCUAUUCACAGAGACAGGGAACUACACAGUGACGGGAUUGAAACAAAGACAACACCUUGAGUUCAGCCAUAAUGAAGGCACUCUCAGUUCAGGCUUCCUACAAGAAAAGGUCUGGGUAAUGCUGGUCACCAGCCUUGUGGCCCUUCAAGGUAUGUCCAAAAGAGCCGUAAGCACCCCAAGCAAUGAGGGUGCUAUUAUAUUUCUGCCACCUUGGUUAUUCUCCAGGAGGAGAAGGUUGGAAAGGAUGUCCAGGGGGAGAGAAAAAUGUUACUCAAGCCCUGGCUAUCCACAGGAAAGUUCAAACCAGUUUCACUGAUCCAAAGGCACUAAGGAGGAAGACAGAUAAAUCAGACUUUUCAAUGGGUAGGAGGUAAGACUCAUUAGGAAUGAAGGCCUGUGAGAGAGGCAAGUUAGUACAACUACCUCUACUCACUGCAUGAACAGAGGGCUACAAGUUGAAGCAACAGAUUUUCAGCUAUUAGAGGAAGAAAAGGCAAGAGACAGACUUGGUUUGGAGAUGGGUUUUGAACAAUGCGGCUCCUCAGCAAAGGCUGAUGGCCAGAUUGAGUAUAUUAAACACAUGUAGCUGAGUCCUCUGAAAACCAUUUACCAAUAUAGAUUAGCGUUUUCCCUAUUAGAUAACAAAAAGUGAAACUUCCAAUAAUUUGUCAUAACGUUUUUGCAUAACAAGCAACUGAUUCAGGUUUUUGCCUGGCCUUGGCAUUCUUAACUCCAUUUUAUUUAGGCAUUCCUCAAAUCAAUAACUACCACUGUUUUGAAUGGCAUCAGAAUGUAAGCUCUAUAUAUAUGUAAGGACUUUGUCUUCUUUACCCCAACGAAAAGUCCCACACAUAUGGCAGGCUCUUAAUAAAUUUGUUAAAAAACCUGUAUGAUGAAUCAGAUGCUUUACACAUGAUGAUUCUAACCUUAUACAACCCUUGCAAGCAAACAUCCCCUGGUUACUCAUCAGGAAACAGACACAAGGAAGUUAAAUAGGGCCUGGUGCGGUGGCUCACGCCUGUAAUCCCAGCACUUUGGGAGGCCAAGGCAGGCAGAUCCUUUGAGCCUAGGAGUUUGAGGCCAGUCUGGGCAACAUGGCAAAACCCCAACUAUACAAAAAAAUACAAAAAUUAGGCAUGGUGGCACACAACUGUAGUCCCAAGCUAAGGCAUGAGGAUCACCUGAGCCCAGGCUGGUUGAGGUUGCAGUGAGCCAUGAUCAUGCCACUGUACUCCAGCCUGGGUGACAGGGUGAGACACUUUCUCAAAGGAAAAAAAAAAAAAAAAAGAGUUAAUUGUUGCCCGUCACAGCAAUUAAUACAGAUCCUUCUCACUCUAAAACCUUACACUCAGUAAUGAUCUACUAUAUGCAAAGCACCUCUUACAUCCUUCACCACCCCAUUCAUUCUGAGAUUGACUCCUCCCCUUUCCAGAAACAGGACCACCUAAACAUUCCCUAUUCCAGUCCCUUAUUUGCAAGUCAUCAAAAGAAAACAGAGAUUUCAAAAAGAAAACAGAGACCUUAUCUGUAAUCCUUGGUAAGGAUCUUCCAAAUUUAAGCCUAUGCCAGUUUUCAGGAGGAAACAUGAAUAUGAAACAGUCUGACCUUUAGACAUAAUUUUUUGUUGACUUUAAAUUCCCUUGGUUAGGCCACUGUAACCAGUAAAAUAAAUUUUAUUUUAGAAUAAAAAUUAUAAAGGGGAAAUUGAGUCUAGCCAUACAACCUACUACUAGUUACUAUCUUUGAUUCCCAAGUCAUCCUAGAGCAAAAAAAAAAAAAAAAAAAUCAUCUCUGGCCUUUUUUUCCUUUUCCACUCAGGUGAAGAGAAUGAGCUUUUGAAUCCAAUUUUUUGUUUUCUCCUAUAUUCAAUUCAAGUAGCUUUAAAGUUAACCAAAGGAAAAAACCAAAGCUCAAUAUUUGAUUAAACGAGAAAAUAUACACUACUUAGAAGCUUUCUUUUCUUUAUCCUUCUUCCCCAACUCAAGGCUUAGUAGAAUUAUUGAAAGAGGUAGUAUUCAGUAGAAUAGUACACAUGCUUUUUCAGGUCCAGAAACACCACAUAGGUCAAGUUAUCAUGCUUACAUGUGGGGAAAAGGAGGAGGGAGUUUCCUGGACCUCUGUGCCUCUCUCAGCUCAUGAACUAGUUUCAGUGAAUAUCCUUGUCUUACCACUGUGCCAACAAUUCAGAGCUAUACGUGGAAAACCUACCUUCAACUUUUUGAGUGGCAUCUAUUGCUUCUUUGAUUGUUCCUUCCAGCAAGGAGCGAUCAAAGGCUAGCCCCCUUCCCACUCCCACCAGAAUCAGAUUUGCUCAAGAUUACAACCCUAAUUUAGUAAUAAGAUGCAAUACAUAAAAUAGUUCCCACUUUCCUUUUCCAAUCCCUUUACAGUCAUGAGGGCCUAUCACGCACGCAUCUCAGGACAGGUGAGACUUCAUUAUAUCAGGUAUUUUGUUGCUAUUCUAAGUUAUAAGGCAGUAAUACAAACUUUCUUUCCACAGCUUUGUAAGCCUUGUGCCAAAAGAAACUUUUAAAACAGCUACAGCAAGAUGAGUCUGACUAUGGCUUAGUAUCUUUCUCAUUACAAUAGGCACAGAGAAGAAUGCAACAGGGCACAGGGGAAGAGAUGCUAAAUAUACCAAGAAUCUGUGGAAAUAUAAGCUGGGGCAAAUCAGUGUAAUCCUUGACUUUGCUCCUCACCAUCAGGGCAAACUUGCCUUCUUCCCUCCUAAGCUCCAGUAAAUAAACAGAACAGCUUUCACCAAAGUGGGUAGUAUAGUCCUCAAAUAUCGGAUAAAUAUAUGCGUUUUUGUACCCCAGAAAAACUUUUCCUCCCUCUUCAUCAACAUAGUAAAAUAAGUCAAACAAAAUGAGAACACCAAAUUUUGGGGGAAUAAAUUUUUAUUUAACACUGCAAAGGAAAGAGAGAGAAAACAAGCAAAGAUAGGUAGGACAGAAAGGAAGACAGCCAGAUCCAGUGAUUGACUUGGCAUGAAAAUGAGAAAAUGCAGACAGACCUCAACAUUCAACAACAUCCAUACAGCACUGCUGGAGGAAGAGGAAGAUUUGUGCAGACCAAGAGCACCACAGACUACAACUGCCCAGCUUCAUCUAAAUACUUGUUAACCUCUUUGGUCAUUUCUCUUUUUAAAUAAAUGCCCAUAGCAGUA